AGUCACCGCCGCCGCGCGCCAGAGAGAAGCAGCCUCCGGCCCCGGCGGCCCCUGUCUCCCGACCCCGGAAGGCGAAGCAGGCUGCCCGGGGACCCCGCGCGUGGGCGCUUGAAGCCGAGACCAGCCUGCCCGGGCCUGGGCAGGCGGAGCAGGGCCUUGGACCCCGCGGCGCCCCUCGGCCUCGGAGCAACGAGCGCAGCGCCGGUGGGUGACCCUCGGGGACGGGCGGGCUGCUCUGCCGCCUUUGUCUCUGUGCCCCUCCGAGUGGGGACCGCGGAGACCUGGGCGGGACCCCGGACCGGAGCCCCGCGGGAGCCGGGGGCGCAAGAUCGGGGACAGGAGCUAUCCCGACGCCCGGACUCCGGGUCCCUUUCUUGGCUGGGGACGCGCAGGGAGAACCUAGGCAGCGGAGCAGGUGGCCGAGCAGGUAGCAGCCGGCGGCCUCCCUGACCCGAACCCAAGUCGCCGCCCCCGAUCCCCAUUGCGCGGGGGCUGGGCGCGGGUGUAGACGCGGGUUUACAGCGCCGGGGCCCGACCCUGACAGGUGUCCAGGGGUGGACUCCAGCCAGGCCCGGCGGUCCCAGGGUCGCUGAAACCGCUCGGCCUCGGGCCGUGGGGCUGAGGGGAGGAGUCUAGGGUGGGAGGGGACGGCGGUCAAAAGCGGCCACUCUGGGCGGGUGUGGAGAGGGUGCUGGCUGCCAGGGCGGGCUGGGGGGUCCUCCCGGCUCGCGGCGCCUGCUAAUCACACCCCGGGGGCCCCGCGCGCGAUCGCGCUCCUGCCCCUGCCCCCGGGGCGAAGCGCAGUCUCCCUCUGAGCUCCAGGGGCGGCCAGGAGAGCCCGGGUCCGGGCUUCCGCCUUCGCAGGGCCUGUCUCGGGCUCUUCGGCCGGGCCCGUCGCUGCGCCCACCUGGGCCCACGUGCGCCGCCCGCAGCCGCCCGCCGGCCCGCCCGGGUCUUCCCGGCAGUCCCCUCCUGGGCCCCACUGCCUGUCCUGGGCCGGGUGCGUCCGUUUUCCGUGGCCCCCGAGGCCGGGGUGUGUGACCUGCGGUCAUUUGCCGCCACACUAGAUUUUCCGGGGUGCUGGGGGCAGCGCCUUGUGUCCUUUCGCGUCCACCUGAGCCCCCCCGUUUUGGAAGGUGGAGUGGGGCUUGGGAAAAGGUUCAAGCGUCUUUGGGGACCCCCGUGCGACUCUGGCUGGAAACAGGCGAGCUCUGGUUCCUUGUUCCGUUUUCCAAUUGCAACAACGUGAGAAUCAACAAGUGCUCGGUUUCUCUGCGCGUGGGUGAGGGGCGCGUGGGCUCGCUGGGUGCUGGGGUGGGGAGGGGGCGUGGACUUCGUUCCGGGGAGGCCUCUGCCUCGUCUGACCACAGAACGCCCCGCCUGGAAAGAGAGUUUUUCAGAGGAAGGAAACGUCAGGGAACUCCAGUGUGUGUUUUGGACAUUUUAUCUGGCGAAGCUCCGGGGGACAGUUUAAGGACGGUCACCCUCAAGUCAGGGGACCGUAUGGAUUGAGCAGGUCCCGCACUGAGCUCCCUGGCGGCCACCUCCAGUGAUGAGCACCUCCUUAGCGGUUGGGGCCGGGGCUGUGGUCACGGCUGAGAGCCUGGAACCCAGCCGCCCUUCAGUGGAGGAAGGCCAGGGGAAGGGUACCGCGGCAGAGGGGGUGUGUGUGUGUGUGUGUGUGUGUGUGUGUGUGUGCGCGUGCGUGCGCGCGUGUGUGUGUUUUGUUUUUUGAGGUUUUGUUUUUUUUUUUUUUUUGUGGGAAAAACAGAAAUCUGAGGGAAAAGAACACAGUUAAAAAUUGCUGUAAAUGCUGGAGUAACUCCCAGGGAGUUAACUGUUCUGAAACAACCACUUCUACUAACUCCGGGUUAAACAAAGCUAUUUUGUUCAAAUCCUCUUUGAAAAUCCUCCAGAAGUAUCACAGUUCUGCCCAAAGAUAAGAAAGUGUAAGACACGUCGCUUGUUUUACACCUGGUAGCUCAUGGCUCCUCCAUGAUUUAAAACGUCGGGUUUGAGUUUGGUCAGUGGUGGUCCUAGCUGUGUGCGCUGAUUAAAGGUAGCCACGAAACGCUGGGGAAAAAAGAAAAAAAAAAAACAAGAGACCAAACUUUCUUGUGAUGUUUCUAUUUCUGCCUGAAUUUGUAAAUGUUAAUUGUAAGUUAUUUUGUUUGACUUUUAAUCCUCCUCCAAGUUCUUUAAAAAUAUGACAUGCUUAAGAUGAGCAGCUGCCUCUGUGCCUUUUCUGUCGCCUGGGAGUGUUUAUCGACUGCUUGCACGUUGCCAGACUCUCUUUUGAGAGCGGUUUGUCACCUCGGAUAACAGUCGGGACGGCCCUAGGAUGCCCUCACUGGAUGUCACCAUCCUAUUCAUAUCUUCAUUUUUUACUGUUGAGGAAACAAGGCCCAGAGAGGUUAAGUUACUCUAAGGGCACACAAGAAGAGGCGGGAUUCCAUCCGGGGAGUCUGCACCAGCGCCUGACUGCUGCUCUGCACCGCCGUGGUGAGAAGGAUGCCUUGCAAAGGUGCUCCUCGUUCCUCCUUUUAAAAUUCCACCCCAAUGAUGAGUGAGUGUACCCAGAGAUGUCCCACACAGGUUUCCUUUCAAGAAUGAUUUCACCAUAAGGCUACUGUCAUCCGUCUUUGUUCAUCAUCUUCUCCUUAGCUUUCUUAGUUGUCAAUAAAAAAGAAAAGAAAAUAUUCUAAUUACUCCUUUUCUUUUUCUUUUUUUUUUUUUUGACAGAGUCUUGCUCUGUCACCCAGGCUGGAGUGCAGUGGUGCAAUCUCGGCUCACUGCAACCUCCACCUUCUGGAUCCAAAACAGUCUCCUGCCUCAGCCUCCCCAGUAGCUGGGACUAUAGGGGCGCACCACCACACCUGGCUGAUUUUUGCGUUUUUUUGUUUGUUUUUGUUUUUUAGUAAAGAUGGGGCCUCACCAUGUUGGCCAGGCUGGUCUCAAACUCCUGACCUCAAGUGAUCCACCCACCUCGGCCUCCCAAAGUGCUGGGAUUACAGGCAUGAGCCACCGCGCCUGGCCUCUAAUUACUCUUGGGAUAAUUUUAAAUAAGUGGCCAUUAAGUAGUAAGACACUUCUGUUGGCCCAUUGGAACCCGUGAAGGAAGCUCUGGAGCUGUUUAAGGGAAGAGUGCUCAUGCCACAGGCCCUAAUGCCAGCUGAGCAGAAAUGCCAGGCGAGUAGCUGGAAUAGUCUCUACAGGAGAUUUUAAAUCUCUGUCAAAACCUGUAGUGGACAGGCUUCAUCCAGAGAAACAGAAGCAGGUGGAGAUACACAUUAGAGACUCAUGGCAAGGAAUGGCUUAUGCAGAGGUGGGCUGGCCAGGUUUGUGGGACGUCUGUAGGACAGGCCAGCCAGAAGGCAGCUGAUCUCCCCGGCCGACUGAAGCUGCCUUCCACAGCAACAUCUCCCACAUGCCAGCAACAACCACGAGUGCAUGUUCCAAAGCUAUUAGUAAUGUCUCACACUCAAUAGCCAUUAAAGCGUAAAAAUGUCAUUCCGAAUGUUCUUUUGUUCUGGACUCUGUGAAUAGCACUGCGUUGGUCUGAGUCACCAUUGUGAAAAAUAGGUGGAUAUCUAAAAGAUGAGGAGAAACAGACCUAUGUGAGGCCAGGAUCUAGAAUACAGAAACAGUUCUAAAAUGUGGUAAUUUGAAACAAGCCACUCAAGAGUAAAAUAUGAGACUAAUGAGAAAACCCAGAUGGACUGAUAAAAUAAGAAAAGGACUUUAACCCUCUGGGAAUCAGGGAAUUCAAAACUAAGAUGGCAAAAAGAUUUUUUUUUACCUUUACGGUACUGGAAAAAAAUUUAAAUUGUGACUAUACCAAAUAUUAGAGAAGGUGUAGAAAACUUAGACCUCACAUGAGUUCGACUAGAAUGUAAAUAGGAACAAAGAUGUUAGAGAAUAAUCUAGAAAAAGUGAAGGUGGGUGUAUCCUAAGAUCUAACAAUUCCACUUCUAGGUAUCUCCUCUAGGGAAAACCUGGUCUGUGUGCAUAAGACACACACAGUGGAUAUUCACUGAAGCAAUGUAGUAAAACCCUGUUUUGAGAUCAUGUAGAUUCACAUGCAAUUCCCUUCACCAGUUUCUCCCAACAAUAACAUCUUACAAAACCAUAGUACAAUGCCACAACUAGAAAAUGAGCAUUGAUACAACCCAUUAACUUUGUUCAGAUUUCAGAUUCCACCAGUUUACAUGUACUCAUUUUAUAGACUGCUCUGUGUGUGUGUGUGUGUGUGUGUGUGUGUGGUAUGCACGUGCGCUUAGUUCUCUGUAAUUUUAUCACCCAUGUAGAACCAUGUGACCACCAACACAUCAGAGGACAGGAGAGUUUCAUCACAGGAUCCUUGAUGCUACUCUUUAUAGCCAAGCUGACUUCCUCCUUCCCCCUCCCUGAGGCUGGCAACCACAAUGCUGGCCUUACCACUCGGUGAUUAUUUUCUACCACUUUAUCUUGUUUUUUCACCCUCUUCACAGAGUCCUUUGCAGAAAGUUUUACAUUUUGUUGAAUUCAAGUUUAUUAAUUUUACCUUUUUUGGAUUUUGAUUUUUGGUGUGAAGUCUAAGUCUUCACCUAGCCUGAGGUUCCCGAAGAUUUUCUCCUUUUUUCCCUACAAAUUUUAUAGUUUCACAUUUUAUACUUAAGCCUAUUUUCCAUUUUGAGUUAAUUUUUGUAUGAGGUGUGAGGUUUAGGUUGAGGCUUAUUUGUUUUGGUUUGGUUUGGGUUUUGCCAACGAAUGUCCAAUAGCUCCGGGACUAUUAGUUGAAAAGGUGAUCCUUCUUCCAUUAAAUUGCUUUUGCACCUUUGCUAAAAACCGUUUCCACUUAUUGCUGUGGGUCUAUUUCUGGGUUCUCUAUUCUGUUCCAUUAGUCUAUAUGUCAGUCUCUCUGCCAAGAGCACACUGUCUUGAUUACUGUAGUUGCAUAGUCAACUUUAAUCAGGUGGAGUGACUUCCUUCCACUUUAUUAUUCUUUAUAAAACUUAUGUUAGCUAUUGUAGGUUCUGGGCCUUUCCAUAUGAAUUUUAGAAUAGCGCGUUUAUGGGUGCAAAAACCUUGCUGGGAUUUUGAUAGGAAUUUCUUCAAAUGUAUAGAUUAGGGAGAAUUAAUAGUUCUACUGUGUUGAGUUUUCCAAUCCAUGAUCACAGGUUGUCUCUCUAUGGGUAAUUAGGUCUUCUUUAACUUCUUUCAUCAAUGUUUUAUAAAUUUCAGUGCACAGAUUCUGAAUCUGAAAUUUCUUUACAGUGUACAUAAGUGUUUUAUUUUCUUUGGGGCAUUUCUAAAUGGCAUUGUGUCUUAACUUCAGUUUCCACGUUUAUUGUGGAGUAGGUAGAACUGUGAGUAAUUUUUAUGUGUCAGUCCACAUUCUGCAACCUACUGAGCUGCCUUAUUAGAUCUAGGAGGAUUUUUUUUGGUAGAUUUCUUGGGAUUGUCUAUGUAGAUCAUCAUGUUAUCUGCAAAUUGGAUAGUUUUAUUUCUUCUUUCCAAUUUAUAUACUUUUUAUUUCUUUUUCUUAUCUUACCGUACUGGUUAGAAUGUCCAGUGCUAUAUUCAAUAAGAGUUGCAAGAACUUGCCUUAUUCUGACCUAAAGGGCAAAGCACUGAGUUUUUACCACCAAUUAUGAUGUAGCUAUAGGAUUUUUAUGGAUGUUCUUUAUCAAGUCAAUAGUCCAUGUCUAUUCAUGAAUGUGUGUUGUAUUUUGUCAAAUGUCUUUUCUGGGACAAUUUAUAUGUUCAUGAGAUUUUUCUUCUUUGACUUCAUGGUAUGAUGGAUAGUUGAUUGACUGACUCUCUAAUGCUGACCCACCCUUGAGUAUCUGAUAUAUAUUCCACUUAGCCAUGUAUAUAACUUUUUUAUGUGUUGCUAGAUUCACUUUACUAAUAUUUUGUUGAGGACUUUUGCCUCUAAGUGUUUGUGAGAUAUUGAUCUAUAGUUCUCAUUUUUUGUAUAGUCUUUGCUAGUUUCAGUAUCAGGAUAACUGGCCUCAUAAAAUGAGUUAGAAAGUGUUCCCACUUGUUCUAACUUUUGGAAGAGAUUGUAUAAAAUUGCCAUAAAUUUCUCCUUAACUGUUUUAGUAGAAAUUUCCGGUGAAACCAUGUGGGCCUGGGGAUUUCUUUCUUGGGUAUUUCCUUCCUUCUACUUUGUUUGUAUAUAUUUAGCUCUUUUUUUUUUGGUUUCUUGAAUUAGAUCUUAGAUUAUUGAUUUGAGACUUUUCCUGCUUUCUAAUAUAAGUAUUUCAGGGUAUGAAUUCCCUCUCAGCACUACUGAACUAGGUGUACAUAUUUUAUCGAGUAAAAGUUUUGAUACAAAAAAAAAGGAGGGAAACACACUAAUUCCCCAUGAGUAGGGCUAUAGAUUUACGCUAUGAUUUACUUACAACAGUUAAACUACCCAGACUUUGUGUAUCAACAUGGACAAAAUUCUAAAUAACAGUGUUGAAUGGAAACCAGCAAACUGCAAAUGAAUAUAUAUAGUAUUAUUCUAUUUCUUUAAAAUUUUCAAAUCCACAAAAGAACAUGUGGUCAUGAUUACGUGGGAUUAUAUGACAUAUAGAAGCCAGGUAAUGUUAUCUUCUAAUCUCGGGGAGGGGAGGGAAUUGGCUGUCUCUGCAUGGUUUUAUUUCUUAAAAAUAUUUUGAGAUUUUAUACAAAUAACAGAAUGUGUUACUUUUUUUGAUGAAAAGGAUAAGCCAGUUGUCUUGUAGAUUAUUAUCUGUGCUUUUUAAUAUGUUCGAACUAAUUAGUAAUUUAUAUUAGCAAUAAAUAAACCAAUGUAAAGUUUGGGGGGAAAUGACACCAGCGAUAAUGAAGUGUUAGAGAGGAAGAUUAGAAGGCCCCACAAAGGAAUCUGAAAGCAGGUGUGGAGGUGAAAUUACUGAAAUUUGGUAAGAGCAUGACAAUGACAAGGAAGGCGAAGGAGAGGAAGAAGAAAGGGCAGGAGAGACAGUCUCCCUCCUCUUCGUUGUCAUUUGUUCAAGUAAUAUAAGUGCAGAAAGGAAGGAUAAAGAAAUUGAUCUAAAAAGAGAAGCGUGCAGAAACGGGCAGGAGCCGGGACCUCAGAGGAGUGGGCUGGAUUCAGCACAGGCCUGGGGAUUAACUAGGUGUUUGCAACCUCACUCUUGAGCCCAUGACUUGAGGAAGAACCAUGAGAAUCUAGCUAAAUCUGAAAAGAUUUAAGGAACAAAAUUUGUAUGGGGAUCCAGCCCUUUUUCCUUCUUGGCUGCCAGGAUUUAUAAUGAGCUGGGCCUCUAAGAGCAGUCUAGCAUGAUUCAGACAGAGGCCAGCAAACCAGGGCCCCACUUCCUGUCACUCUGCAGGCGACCUGGCUCAGAAACUCUGGAGGUAAAGUGUGGCUGCCCGCUCAACAGCCUCAGGAAGUCCCCAAAGCCCUAUCUCCUAUCUCCUGUGGGUGGGCUCUCCCCCACUGGCCCCGAGGGAGACUUUGCUCCUUUCCUCUCCCAUCCCCUCCGAACUCACCUGAGACAGGCACCCAGGCCAGUGCGGCCCCAGCUGCCCCGCGUCCAACCCCCACUUCCGGGGGUGCAGCUGGGGAAGGAGGUGCAGGCAGCGACCACAGCAGCUACUGAGCCCCAAGAAAGGAGGCCAGCACGGGGUGGGGGGUGGGAGGCGUGGUGGCCAGAAGAGUUAUUCUAGCGAUUUAUGUUUACAUCAAUUCACUUCCUUUAAGAGUAAAGGGAUUAAUAUUCAGCUCCCCAAUUUUCCAAAGGUCAAGAAAGAAAAUGAAGUUUUAUUCAUAGUAAGUGAUUAACCAAAUUACCUGUUUAAUUUUACAUUAGAGACCACAUAUACAAUGUAUAAAAAGGCAAGUAAUAAAGAGGAGAUAGAACAUGGAAACAAAGGACCCAGAGGCAGAGAUGAGGGGGAGGCAGGAGGCUGGAGAAAGGGAGGUUUCUCAGCAGUUCAGGGGACUGCUGGUGUUGCGGCCCGUCUUUUGGGGCAUCUGGUGACACGGGAUGCUCCCAGAGAGCCCUGCUCCUUCCAGGUAGGAAGGUGUGCCCAUGCUGCCCUGCAGGCAAGAGCAAAAUGCCCUGUGCUGGGAAGGGAUGGAGCUCAGGGCAGCUCCACCCGCAGACUCCGUGCAGGUGCCCUAGGCUGCUUCCCGGCUGACCACCAACCCAGAGAGACAGAGAAAUGCUCUACUCAGAUCUGCUUUUCACCUGGAGCCUGAUUAAGAAACCUAAAGCUCCAGAGGUCAAUACACACGGAAAACAAAACAAAGCUACCUGGAUCAGUUUAGAGUCCUAGCAGGGACAGAAUUGCCUUGGUGGCUGGACGCCCAACUCCCAAGCCAAGCAUCUGCCGUGGCCCCCUGACCUGCUCACCAGGAGAGGGGACAAGCUGGCUCCUGUGGUCUGCAGCCACCUGCACACAUUACACUGAGAAUUCAAAUUAAAUGCAGAGUCCUAGGCCCACCCUGGCAUACCACCCCACAGUCUUGGGGUCGGGCCCAGGAAUAUGUAUUUUAAUGAGCUCCGGGUUAACUUAGGAUUGCUGCUGUAAGUGAAGGAAGGAAACAGACCGUGAGUGCCUCGGUGUUUCCAGGUCGACACAGCUCAUCUGAAUAGACCCACACAAGCUCUCAAAUGUGUGCUUUCAUGUGAUCAGGAAGUCCUUUCUGUUUCACUGAUAAAUUGAAUUUGCAUUAGAAUAACUAAUUGAUACUAAAGCUUUUUGUUGACAGUUUAUUUUUAUUUGCAUCAUGUAUUUUUGAUGCUUUUUCCAUAUUUAGAGAAUAACAUUUUAUGUCCUGCGUGAGUCUUCAUCUGAUGAGGAACGUUUAUGGAUACUCAUUUUCUUCAUCUUUCUUGUAUGGUUGAAAGCUACCAUGUUUGCUAAACUUGCUAUCAAAGCAAAAAAUUAUAGAACUAUGUUGUAGGCUCCUCACAUACAGCAAACGUACCAUUACUUUUUAAAAAUUCCUUGGUGUCUACUGUGUACAAAAAUACUAUGCCGUCCAUUUCAGGGUAUGUUAAGAGAAAAUAGAUGUCAUUCUUGCCCUUGAAGUGCUUAUAGUUUUAUUAGGAAGCUUAGAAGUUCCCAAGUAAUUUUCCCAUGGCAAAAUAUUUGCUCAAUACCCUGCCAUGUAUACAAAAUGCUGCUGGCUUUCUAAAGAAGGGGGUUGUGCUCGGUAGAGGAGUAGAGUAGACUGGAUGAUGACGACUAGAACUGGCAGAAUUAUGUUGAAUGGAAAAUAUACUAGCCGGGCGCGGUGGCUCAUGCCUGUAAUCCCAGCACUUUGGGAGGCCGAGGCGGGAGGAUCAACUGAGGUCAGGAGUUCAACACCAGCCUGACCAACAUGGUGAAACCCUGUCUCUACUGAAAAUACAAAAAUUAGCCAGGCGUGGUGGUGGGCGCCUGUAAUCCCAGCUACUCGGGAGGCUGAGGCAGGAGAACUGCUUGAACCCGGGAGGCGGAGGUUGCAGUGAGCCCAGAUUGCGCCAAUGCACUCCAGCCUGAGUGACAGAGCAAGAUUCUGUCUCAUAAAAAAUUUAAAGAAAAGAAAGAAACAAAAUACAGUGUAACGUUUUGCUGUCUUCUAUGCCGCAGUUCACUUCCCACUUGGCCUCCACUGUCCCGGGAGCUGCCUGAGCGUCUCCCAGCUUGCCCAUCUGAGAGACUUCUCGGGACUCUAGCUGAGACUCUAGCUGGGAUUCCCAGCUCAUCAUUGGCGUAGUCCACUCCUUUCUGGAGUCGCCUCCUUGCCCUUGUUUCUCAGCUGUCUCCUUCCUUGCACAGCUUCCAAAAAGGAUGGCUGUCUUCUCCAGUUUUGGUAGCAUUUUGUUUACAAGGGGCUUAAAUGCUACAUUGCAAACGUCUGUUCUGGAAAACUGUUAAAACAUGUGUUAGCCCCCACUGAUGUCUACCAUAGUGCACAGUCCCUAAUACUUGUUGCAUAAACUGAGGCGGAUUCUGCCAGUUCUACUCAUCAUCAUCCAACUGAUACACAGCAAGAGCCUAUACUUUCCAGAAGUCAUGUGUCUAAAUCUGUUCUCCACCAAUCAGAAGCUAAAGACCUGGCAUGAUUUAUUCAGCUUAAAUUGUUGCCUGAAAAUACCAGAUAAAUUAACUCAGUAAUUUGACAAAAACAACAACAACAAAGACUCUCACAUAUUUGAGGAGCUGGUUUUCUCUUACAUGGGGUUGUGGCAGGCUGUGUGUUCCAGGUGUUUUUAUUCCUGUUCUUUCGGCUAUCUGAAAAUGUAAUAACCUUGGGACAGCUUGAGAGCAAGAUUUAUGAAGUGUGAGCACCAGCUACAGCUGGUCUUUCUAGAAAUAUAAAGAGAAAUAUAAAUAUAAAUAUAAAUCAAUUGUAUUUCAGAAACAGGCAUAGCACGUCUGUGGACAGCUUCAAUAUAUCAUUUUAGAUUGCUGUAUGAAAGGCAUUGUGAGUUUUAAAGGGAGAUGAUGACUCUUUUAUUCUGUCAUUAUUUUCAUAUGCCGAGACAUAUUUGAAGACAGGAGGAUUUAAGCAAGAUGUUAGAAGCUCACCUUAUUCAUUUCAGACUAGUGGUUGAAAAUGGGUGUAUGCAGGGCGGGAGAACUCAGAAGAGCUGAGGCCUGGCAGCAGCCUUCCUGAACACGCAUGUUUAAAUGUAUGUGAAAUGCCAGGGUUAAAGCCUCAUUAGGAAAGAGUCCUAACACUAAAACACACGGCUAGAUAAGCAACACCAAAAUAACACGUACUAUAGGAACUUAAAGUAAAAAUCUUAUUUAUUUAUUUUUUUUUUUUUGAGACACAGUCUCCCUCUGUUGCCCAGUCUGGAGUGCAGUGGUGUGAUCACAGCUCACUGACCCCUCAAUCUCUGGGGCUCAAACGACCCUCCCACCUCAAUCUCCCUGAGUAGCUGGGACCACAGACAGGCUCACACUGCCACACCAGGCUAAUUUUUGUAUUUUUAUUUUUUGUGGAGACAAAGUCUCUCCAUGUUGCCCCAGCUUGUCUCGAACACCUGGGUUCAAGGGAUCCUCCCACUUGGUCUCCCAAAGUGCUGGGAUUACAGGCGUGAGCCACUGUGCCCAACCUUAAAUUUUAAUGGGAGGUACAUUAAAAUGUGGAUUACGUUUCACACAAUUUCAAAAACAAAACAACUGCAUUUGCUCAAGAACAUAGAAAAGGUCCUGGCGGUAUUUUUGUAUGGGUUGAUCCUCACGGGGUCCUAAAUCUUGUAGAUUCAACUUCGUUUGUUUUUACAACAUGUGUAGAAGAGGAAUUUGAAAAAUUUACCGAUUGCACACACACAGGUUUAUUCCUGACCUCUUUCCAUGGAGUGACACUUAAUUACCAUGACACCUGUGCUCAGAGGACAGCUCCAAAGGUCGGUAACGUGGUUUUCCGAAUCCCAAUAUUUCCCCAUCCUUUUCUCGGGUGAACUUUUCUUGCCACUCUCUCUGGAAUUUUCUGCUGCUGGUGCGAUAGACCUCGUGACUAACAAUGCGUUUUGUAAAAUAGUCUGGAGGCCCAGAGAAAGCCAGAUAUGAAAACUGGCAGGGAGAAGCCAGGCAGAGGGCAUUCAUUCAUUCAUCAUUCAUUCAUUCCUUCAAGCAGGCCUAGCUCAGGCCCAAAUCAGCGCCUGGGGGGCUUCCUGAAAGGAAGAAAAACACCCCACGCUGAGGUCUUUGUCCCGGGUCAGUGCAGGUCUGAAUGCCUGAGUGCCUCUGGGCGUCACAGCCCCACUUCACAGCUGCCCCUCUGCAGCCUCCCAGGUGUGUGCAGCGCGUCUGAGGUCACCUGGCCGUGCCGGUCACAGCUGCACCAGAUGCCGCGAGGGCUGACCAGAUUUUAGAGGUUUCUAUUUUGCCAGCGUUGGGAGAAGCCUACGGGAGCGUGUGUUCCCUGCAUUAGGACUUUGAGACCCGUAAUGGAUUCACAGAAGAAUGCUCGCACCAAGCGAGAGCGAACCCUUUAGCAUACCUCACCCGAGACAAGGCGGGAUUCAUGCUUCGUGGGCUGAGCACGGCUGUGCUCUUCCUAAAUUGCAGGUCCUGCUCUGUCUCUGGAGACAUUGGGGUCUGUCCCACCCUGUUAGGGUCCCUGUCUGCCCUGGAGGAGAGUCACCUGGGGGUGGCCUGGGCCACUGCAGCUGCUCCCACUGCGCCCAGGCCUCUCCCGUGGCUGCCCCAGGGCCCUCUCUGUCUCCUGGGGACUUUGCAGCUGAGGCUUCAGCCUCAAGCUCAGGGAAGGGAGCUGGUCCACAGCCACGACCACCUUGACUUUCUCUGAGUCCCUUCUUCCGCAGCACCCCAACUUCGGUGCCAAGCCCUAUUUCCUCAGGAGGCUCACACACUUCCCUUGGGGUGUCCCUUGUCCCUCCAGAAUCAAGGCUUCGGUUUUCUGGGAGGAGCCUUAAGUCCUGGCUCCUGCUCUCGGCUCCCUGGGGCUCACCAGGUGGUCUCUUCUCCAGACACACAUGGAGGGUGUUGAGCUGUGUGGGCGCGGCUUGAGGUAAGAGGGAAGAGCAAGCACUUCCCUUGCCAUUCUCUCAUCCACUUGACAGGCAUUUGUCAAACACUUGCUGUGUGCCUACUGUGUGCUGUGUGCCUGCUGGGUAUUGUGUGCCUACUGUGUGUCAUGUACCUACCAUGUACCAUGUGCCUGCCAUGUGCUGUGUGCCUACUGUGUACCAUGUGCCUGCUGUGUGCUGUGGACUGUGCUAGGUCCUGGGGACACCAUGGUGACAAGACAGAGACCCGGCUGGGUGUGCUCUCCUGUGGCAGGGGUGGUGAUGGAGUACACGUGGGGAUGGGGAAGCAGAACAGUGCUCGGGCAGUGACACAGUGGCUCUUCUCAGCACCCCACAGGGUCCUGGUGGCUUCCAGGACACCUCCGGCCCUCUCCCGAGGCUUCCAGGUCCCCAAGCCCCUGCCUGUUCUGGGCUGGGGCAAGUGACACCUCCACUACACAGCUCCAAGCCAUGGCUGCCCCAGCUCCACCUCAGGGACCUGUGGGACCAACUGUGGUCUUCGCUUUCCCCUGUCAGCUGCCCUCACAGACAGGGUGCAAGGGAAAGUGUGUCUGCCGGGCAGCGUCUCACAGCCAAGGGUAGUGUGAGUGUGUCCUUCCAGCGCCCUGGGACAGCAGGAAGGAGCACCAUGUGUGGUAGUGUGUGUGCACAUGGGUGUGUGGUGUGUUGUGGCUGUGUGUGUGGUGUGUGUCUGGUGUGUGUGAAGUGUCUGUGGAGUGUGUGUGUGGUGUGUGUCUGUAGUGUCUGUGGAGUGUGUGUGUGGUGUGCGUAUAGUGUGUAGGGGGUGUGGAGUGUGUGUGGCAUCUGGAGUGUGUGUGUGUGGUGUGUGUGUGGUGUCUGUGAAGGGUGUGUGUGGUAUGCAUAUAGUGUGGGGGGUGUGUGGAGUGUGUGUGUGGUGUGUGUGUGUGGUAUGUAGUGUGUGUGUGUGUGUGGUGUGUAGUGUGUGUGUGUGUGUGUGUGUGUGUGGUGUCUGUGGAGUGUGUGUGUGGGUGGGGCGGGUGGCCUGUGUGUUGGAAUCCAGCUUUCCGCACUGUCUCUGUCUGUGAACCCUGGUGCCGAGCACAGGGCAGACACUCACACGGGAGAUUUCCUGCAUUUCCUCUUGGAUUUGGCCUCCAGUGGGAAAAAUCCAGGUCAGCAGCUCACGGAUCAUGGCCGACUGUGCUAAAACCUGAACAGGCCUGUCCUGUGCCAACUGCUGGGUGCAAAGCCCCCAGAAUCCAGCCCAUGUUGUGAGGGUGGUGGGUGGAGCUCAGAGAGACCAAGCAGUCGGGCUGAGGCCAAUCCACCCUAGGGGAGAGAUGGGGUGGGACACAGGCCUCCUGCUCCCGAACCCACUGACCCCAUCCCACCCCAACCCACUGUCCCCAUCCCACCCCAACCCACUGUCCCCCAUCCCACCCCAACCCACUGUCCCCAUCCCACCCCAACCCACUGUCCCCCAUCCCACCCCAACCCACUGUCCCCAUCCCACCCCAACCCACUGUCCCCAUCCCGCCCCAACCCACUGUCCCCAUCCCGCCCCAACCCACUGUCCCCAUCCCGCCCCAACCCACUGUCCCCAUCCCACCCCAACCCACUGUCCCCCAUCCCGCCCCAACCCCCUGUCCCCGUCCCACCCCAACCCACUGACCCCAUCCCGCCCCAACCCACUGACCCCCGUCCCACCCCAACCCAAUGUCCCCCCUCCCACUCCAACCCACUGUCCCCUGUCCCACUCCAACCCAUCCCACUCCAACCCACUGACCCCCAUCCCACUCCAACCCACUGACCCCCGUCCCACCCCAACCCACUGACCCCCAUCCCACUCCAACGCACCGUCCCCUAUCCCACUCCAACCCACUGCUCAGAGGUUCUGUGCAGUCUCAGGAUGUUACCUACCUCAUUCAAAAUCUGAGAUCAGGGUCAACUAGGAAAUAACCCAUCCACAGAUACUGGAAUUCUGGAGAAGUAUCAAUAGUUCAGACACUUUAUUAUAAUUUCAGGACAGUCACAAUCUAUCAGGCAAGCCACGGAACUAUGAAUGUGUUCUGCCAACGUGUUUGCAUCUUUCAAACCCUGUUCUUUACCCCUUGUGAAAAGCCUUCCUGGAUAAUCUUGAUUUUGAUGUAGGCAUAAAAUUAUAAGGCCUCUACCUAGUGAUAAUAAAUCGUCACCUUUUGAAGGCUACUGAUCUUUUUAGGCCCAAAAAUAUCAUGUAGAAAUUUAAUGGCAUGCAGAAAACACUCGAAAAGUUCAAGUUCAGAAUGCAAGCUCAGUGGCAGUCUUAUGUUCAUAACAUACACCAUGCAUGCUAGGUGUUUAUUAUUGAAUCAUUCAUUUAAAUGCCAUUUUUAAUAACAGAGUUUUAAAAGAUACUUCACUUAAUGACAAAUUCCUAUAGUUCUUCAUAAUUUAUUGUUACUCUGUGAUAGUUUUCAUGUAGAAGGAAAUGAGUUGUGGAGUUGUUACUAUAUUUUGAGUCUUCAGAGCAUACAUGUGACGUGAAGGAGAAAGCACCCUCUAGCCUUUUGAAGGAGGUCUUUUCCGUAAGAAAUCCAGGACUUCAAGUAUCAAGAAACCAAAGACCAGGUCAUCAGGUUGGUGAAGUCACAAACCACGUAGCAGCCAGGAGCACAGCUCAGCUCCGACCUGUUGGUGUUGGUGUCAGGUCCUGCUGUGUGGACUUGUGUUCCUUGGGCUUGCUUUCUUUGUUUGUUUUGUUUUUUUUUUGAGACAGAGUCUCACUCUGUCUCCCAGGCUGGAGUGCAGUGGCCCAAUCUCGACUCAGUGCCUCAGUGCAACCUCUGCCUACUGGGUUCAAGAGAUUCUCCUGCCUCAGCCUUCCCAGUAGCUGGGAUUACAGGCAUGCACCACCAUACGCGGUGAAGUUUUGUAUUUUUAGCAGAGACGGGGUUUCGCCGUGUUGGCCAGGCUGGUCACGCAUUACUCGGGCUUUCUAAACCUCAUGAGUUUCAACGUCUGUAAAGUGGGGAGCAUAAUAAUAGCACUUGCCUCCUUGUACAGUAGACAGGACUAAGAAGCUAUACUUCUGACCUGUUGCAUGAGCACCUAGCCCAUAGUAAGCGCCCCGUCGAUGCUGGCUGCUCUCCAAGCUCUCCUGAGCCCAAAUCUAGUUCUGUUCAAUGCAUCAUUCUGUUUCAUGCUGUGUCUCCUGCCCUUUUCUUUAAAUAUAAUUGUCACUUGCUAGCAUCCUUUGUCUUUCUAAUGUGUCCUGCGAAGUUAAGGACUCACCCGGUAAAAUGCUGCAUGCCCAUGUGAAAACAUGGGGCCCUUUAGGAGAUCAGCUCAGAGCCAGGUCUUUCGUGAGACCAUGGUGAGGUUAAUGACCACACAUUGCAUUCUCUUUCUUGAUUAGAAUCUGGAAGACUCUGGAAAGUUCCAGAAGGUUCUGAAAGGCAGUUGCCCAGUAAAGUGCUGCACACUCAUGUGAAGAUGUGGGGCCCCUCAGGAGACAGCUCAGAGCCAGGUCUUCUGAGGGACCACAGUGAGGUUAAUGACCACACAUUGCCUUAUUUUCCUUGAUUAGAACCUGGAAGACUCUGGAAAGUUCCAGAAGGUUCUGAAAGGCAGUUGCCCAGUAAAGUGCUGCACACUCAUGUGAAGAUGUGGGGCCCCUCAGGAGACAGCUCAGAGCCAGGUCUUCUGAGGGACCACAGUGAGGUUAAUGACCACACAUUGCCUUCUUUUCCUUGAUUAGAACCUGGAAGGCUCUGGAAAAUUCCAGAAGGUUCUGAAAGGCAGUUGCCCAGUAAAAUACUACACACCCAUGUGAAGACGUGGGGCCCCUUAGGAGAUCAGCUCAGAGCCAGUUCUUCUGCAGGACCAUGCUGAGAUUAAUGACCACACAUUGCAUUCUUUUUCUUUAUUGCAAUCUGGAAGGAUCUGGAAAAUUCCAGAAGGUUCUGAAAGGCAGUCACCCAGUAAAAUGCUGCACACCCAUGUGAAGGUGUGGCACUGAUCAGAAGAUGGGCUCUGAUCCAGGUUUUCUUUGAGACCACGGUGGGGUCUGUGGCCACAGCACAGCAUUCUUCUCCUUGAUUAGAAUCUGGAGAUUUCAGAUCAACCACUCUACUUCCCCAUGAUAGCAGCAGAGCUGAACAUCUUUCCUAUCAUGGACUCCGUAAUAGGAACCUGUGUUUUCGGGAAGAUUCAGUUUAUUUUAGCCAAGACCCAGACGACAGCUCUUAUGUGUACGCAUGGCCUGAGCAUGGGGCCAACACAUUUGUUCCCUGCACACAGGCUAUCAAGAGCCAUUGUGCCUGCUGGCAAGGAAUGUGUGAGUUCCUCGGCAGGUGAAUUAAAACAUUCUUCAGUUAACACCAGCUCUGGCUGUGAGCAAUGCCUGAAGUCGGUGUGUUUCCUCUAGUUACUAAGACCAGGGCCCGGGGUCAUGUUGACCCUGUGGAUGGUGGUAUUGGCAAAGGUGUCACUCCCUGCCACGGCUCAGGAGGGACAUACGGGUGGCUACAGAGGAGCAGCUGGUGCCAGCGUGUAGUGUUCCUCUGACUUGACAGUUUGUAACCCAGCGACCUGUAAAAUAUUAACCAGUGGUUUCCACAGCAGCUCCAGGAAGCUGCAUCCACCAUCAGGGCUUUACAGAUAAGGAGGUCAGGGCCCACAUCCUCAGAGCAGACAGGGAGAGCAGGAAUAGGAAGGCCCUCGCCCAGGCACGUCUGCCCCCAGGCCUUCCCCACUUCCUCCCUGCAGCCCACUGCUCGCCCUGUCCCAGCUGCCGGCCCCUGGGUUGGGCGGCUUGCGCACCGCACACUUGGAAAGGGGGCUCAGCAGGACCUGACCUAUGCUCCUGUGACUAAGCCCCACAUGACUGCGAAGCUACCAGGGAUCCCACCGGCCGCAGAGCAAGGGCGUGUCACGUGUGCCUGCGUGACUCUGCCCUCCCCGUGCCAUCCGAAGGCCAGUCCCAGCGUGACGGUGUUGGCAUGGCUUGUCAGGACUUACACAGCAAGAGUGGUUUCCUCAUGACCUCGCUAUUUUUACACAGAGAAUUUCGUAACUCCCCAUAAUGCUGCUAAAGCUGAACACCAUGCCUGUCAUAAACAUGUGGAUACAUUCACAAGGAAUUUCAAAUGCUAAUCUAACUGACACGUGGAUGAGCUACUCUUUGAUCUGCCUUUUUUUCCCCGCUUCAACAAAAUGCUUUGUUUUGGUUUAGACAGCUGAUAUUGUAGCAAGCUAGGAACUCUGGGGCCAGUAAUUUGCUGCUUGAUUCUGAUAAUGGCUUUCUCUCCAAAGUCAGCUGAUCCUGUAAGCAGUAACUUCAAGGGACCACAGUCAGAUUUUCAAUAAACUCCACUUUUCUGCAAUCUCGUCAUUUUCUUUUAAAGUGAUUUUUGAUAACUUUAAAGCAGUGAUAGUCAGUGCCAUAAAUCUACCUGAAUCUGCUAAGGCAGAAGAAAACGAAGGAUGGUGAUGACUAGCUUACAAAUAAUAUUAUCUGAUACCCCAGAGCAAAAAUCCCCAUCCCAGGAAAUAGAGACGCUACUUCCUUAUCAGGCACUUCUUACAUGGGUGAAUGCAAAUUGGGUUUUUGGAACUCUUUGUUUGCAAGUACUGUGGAGCCCCUAGCCCAGGGCUGGCUCCUGAAAACUGCCGGGAGCCUAGGUCCCUCCAGUGUCACGGGGAAGCUUGCUGUAGGACAGACAUGGAUGCCUCAGAUGAGUUUUGACAUUGUCCUUUGCAGAGAAUUCCCGGCUUGCAGGUCGUUCUUCGUCUAGGGCCCAACAGUCUGGAAGACUUGCUCAUGGGCAGAAUUGACUCACUGUUCAAAACGGGUGAAGAACAUUGUCUGUGUGCGUGGUCUAAGUCACUCCCCCAAUCCCCCCAUGAGUGCACCCCGUGCAUUCGCAGAUUCUGUUCUAUUAGGUCACUUCAUGCCACACUCAAACUCCACUCACAGUGUCUGUGCAACAGGGCCUUUGCACAGCCGUGCCCUCUGCCCAGAACGCUGUUUCCCUCCUCAGCACCUUCACCUGCACCUUCUGCAUCCUGCAAGUCUCCACUUACUUCCCACUUCCCUGCAUGUUACCCUGUAGGGCUGCUGCAAGGCGGCACCACAGGUGGGCGUCCUGAAACAGCAGAAGCAGCCCCCCACACACACACAGUCCUGGAGGCCAGAAGUGCAAAGUCAAGGCGUUGGCAGAGUGGGAGCUCUGCAGGAGGCUCUGUCUUCACCUCUUCCAGCUUCUGGUGGCUGCGGCAAUCCCUGGUGUCCCUGGCCUUGUAGCCAUGUCAUUCCAAAUCUCUGCCUCCAUUGUCAUGUGGUGUUUCUCCCUGUGUGAAAUGCCGUGUAUCUAUGUCCAAAAUUCCCUCUCCUUGACCAGGCACAGUGCUGCAUGCCUCUAAUCCCAGCAUUUUGGGAGGCUGAGAUGGGUGGAUCACCUAAGGUCAGGAGUUCGAGACCAGCCUGGCCAACAUGGUGAAACCCCCAUCUCUACUAAAAAUACAAAAAAUUAGCCAGGUGUGGUGGCGGACACCUGUAAUCCCAGCUACUCUGGAGUCUGAGGCAGGAGAUUGCUUGAACCCGGGAGGCGGAGGUGGCAGUGAGCUGAGAUCGCACCAUCGCACUCCAGCCUCGGCAACAAGAGUGAAACUCUGUCUCAAAAAAAAAAAUCCCUCUCCUUUCUCUUGUAAGAACAUCAGUCAUUGCAUUUAGAGCCCACUGUAAUCCAGGAUGACCUCAUCUUAACUUGAGGACAUCUACAAAACCUUCCUUCCAAAUCAGGCCACCUUCACAGGUCCUGGGGUCAGGACUUGGACAUACCUUUUAGGCAGACACGAUCCACCACAUACUAUCCUGGAAGAGUUUCUCGACCUGCACGGUCAGGGUUCGUGGCCACCCACGUGCUCCUAGGCGUUCUCCACACACAUGCCUCCCCUGCAAACAGCCGGCCCCUGUCCUGGCCGCCCGUCUCUCUCCCGGCCUUCCAUGUGGCAGCAGCCUCGAGCUUGUGGGUGGGACAGAGUCCACAGGGAGCUGGAAACAGAGAAGGGGGAGGGGGAGGGAGAUGAGGAAGAGAGGGAUCUGACCCUCCUCCAUAGGAAAACCUCAGCUUCCCCUUUGCACCGAUGUUGGAAAAAACUUCUGCAUCUCCCUCCCCGUUAUGCACGAGGGCUGGGAAAGCCGGCGCACCCAGCGUCAGUGGCGUUCUCCUCAUGUUCGGUUUGCCAUCGUGAUGAACACGCAAUCAGGACAUGUCCGACCUCCCGCAGGUGUGUGUGGAAGGUGGGAACGGGAUGACGGAAGGAGUGUGCAGCGCGCAUCCCACAGCUUUGCCGCCACCCGCCUGGGUGAAACCAAACGCGUCUUCUUCCCACGCCUUGUCCUCAGCUCCGAAAUGAGCUGUUUCUUUUUGCCGCGCGCGCACGUGUGUGUGUGUGUGUGUGUGCGUGUGCACGGUGUUCAUUCUACGGGUUUUUGGUGACGUUGGUAGCUGUGUACUAUGCUCCGAACACAGAGUGUUACAAUCAUACUUUUGGUUUGAGAAAUAAAAAUGAUUGCUUGCAGAACACAGUCUUCAGUGCUUGGGUAUUGGUAGAAUAAGAGGAAGAGGAAUGGAGGGAGGGACGUCGGGGGAGAGAGAAAGGAGACAAGGAUAGUGAAAGAAGAGAAGUCCCGUCACUUGGUUUCAUUUAUUUUCUUUCAGAUAUCUUUGGUUUUAUUUUAUAUAUGAGUUGCUUGUUCUUUGAAAUUUGUUCUCCAGGAUUUCUUUUUCAAAUGUCAAAGAAGCAGAGUUAUAGGGCCUGCCCCUCCGACUUGAGGCUGUCACUGUCCGUGUUCUAGGGGUGAGGGGCUGUUUUCUCUCUGCAGGGAGGGUGGGCGGUGUCUACAGCUCUUACUGAGCCUGCCAAGCCAGGGCGUGGUCUCCCAAGCAGUUACCAACGGCUGAGGAGAUCACCAGGUCUCAGCAUGUUGGUGGUGGCCCUGGUGAAUCCCGCCCUGGGUGCUGGAGAGGAGGCAGAGGCCUCACAAGACCGAGUGGACCUGCCCAGGGCUCACACGACACCAGGGCCCUCCCGUGGGGGUCUCCUUCCUGCAGCCCACAGCCUUCUGCUGCUGCCCCUGCCUGGCCUUUAGCGUCUCUACAAAGGGGCACGACAAUCCUCUGGAAUUUCCACAGUUCCACUGUUUAUUCAGGUUUUCCUUUCCUGGGAUACUGGGUCUGCACCUCUCUCUACCUGAAUUCUACAUGGUAUCUCCUUUAUUAUUUUGCACACAGUUGAGGGGUCAGAGAAGCCUUUUCUGAUGUGUGCAGAUCCACAGUAGCGUUUCCCUUAGUUGCCUUCUUCAAGAAGCUGUAGUCAUGGCACCUCCAAAAUACAGAACCGUGCCCAUGAGCACUGGGCUCCUCGGUGGAUGCUGGGUGAUGCUGUGUUUCAUCUGACGGACCCACAGAGUCGUGUCUUCAGCGUGUAUUUAUGGAGCUUUUCCUCCCAGGCAAACAUUGCCAGGCUUUCUGAACAGGCGCUGAGAACCCCGAGACCCAGCGAGAGGUCUAGCACAGGACUGGAGCAGCCACGAGGCAAUACAGCCAGCUCAGCUUUAAGGUCCCGUACACCGCGAAGACUCCAAAGCACCUGGGAUGUCGAAAACAUUGCUCCUGGGAUUUUAAAAAGCAGAGAAAGCAGAAAAAGAUGCCUUCAUGGUGGGCUCUUCAAAUUCUACUAGCAGAGGCACAAGUUAAGACUUUCCCAAGUGGAUCCUGCUGGUUAGAUUUUAUUAAAUUAACCACAAUUUAUAUGUUUUAUAAUAUAUUCUCAUGUGUCUGUUUAGGUAUAACAUGUUACAGUUUCCAAAUACAGAAAAAAAAAUCUUAUCUAAUUUAUCUGAUGCCUAGGGAAGUGGUCUUAGAACAAAAGUUCCAUACACACUUAUGGAAUGGAGAAAGGCCCCUUGUCCGGCGGUGACCAGCAACAGCUGCAAGGGCUGCUGGGAAAUGUAGUCCCUGCCAGGGCAGCCAGGUGGCCAGUGCAAGGCAGGUGGUGUGGGGAGAGGGGCAGUUCUCUCACUACAUGGAGAAGGGAAGGUGGGGGACUGGGGAGAAGGUCCUUGUGACACAAGCAUGGGAAAUCUCUAUUCUGAAAAAAAAAAAAAAAUUCACAUAUGUCAUAGGUUUUUGCCCCCUGAUCUAUAAGAAGAAGGUUCUCGAACACAAAUCACCUGUAGUGCUUCUGAAAGCAAAGAGUUCAGGGCCCAAGAAUGUGUGUUUCUAAGAAGUUCUCAGGUGCUGAUGGCCGGUCCCCACACCGCAUCACGCUGCCUCGUAUCCGCUUCUGAGACCCUCACCACUGCACACUUCUCUUAUUGUAUUGAUUAAUAAUUUAGGAAUGUAGAAUGUCUUAGGCCUACUGUCAUACUUUCCACAUGGGACAUUCAAAAUGUAAAUAACUCUGUUCAUAACUAAAAUAUAUUCCUAGAGGCAUUCUCAUAGCUAGAUUCAGUCUUCUAAACUUUCUCAACUGUAAAAUGGGAAUGAAGCUUACAGGGUUAUUCCUGUAAUUAUCUAACUUAGGUUUAUAGAAACAUGAGGGAUAAAGCAAAUCAUUGUAAAAUAAAUCCUGUUAUCUCCAUAGAAACAUUACUUUAGGAUUGCUUUCUUGAACAUGGACUCAAAAAAAAACUGUGCAAUCAAAAGCAUGUUAUGAAAACAACGUCCAAAGAAUCCUAAGUCUAAAAGUAACACAAGCGUGAUCUGUGUCCUAUAAUAUGGGUAUACCCUGCAGCUCUACACAAUGCAAAUGUUUUGCUAAUAAGCCUAAACAAAAUGAAGUGCGGAGAGCAUAUGAUGAAUUCCACGCCAUCAUAAACUUGACCUUGCAUUAUGGCACCUGACAUGCUUGUCAGCCUAACCCUCAACAGGCACGAUGUUUGCUCCCUACAUUUUUGCAGGUUUGGGAGUGGGAGUAAGAUGAUUUGGGUAACCAAGUGCCAACUAUCUAGGAAGACUGGCAUUGAGGUCUUCUCUAUCUCACGAUGCAUUUAUUUCUACAAGGGAUUUCACAAUAAUCCCAUUGCUUGUAAAAUUGCACUCACAAUUAUUUCAAAAACAGCCAGUUUCACAUUUUAAUAUUUGAAUACUUGUCUGGCGUUUGGGGCAUGGCUGUCUCGUGAAUGUCCUUCCUCUUCACUUUUUUCCCUCUUUCCUCACCUUCCACACCCCAGGACACUUUGUGUGGUCUUAAAGCAGCAGCAGUUGCAUUUCCCCUGUGCUUCAGUUGUGUGUGUUGGAUCAAGAGCUUUGUUGACAGGCAAUUGUAGGAUGUAACUUCUGGGCAGCUGGUGUUUUUAGCCUUUUUUCUUCCCUUGACCUUGUCAGUUUAGGAGUGGAUGCAUCUAGAUGUGGGAAGCCAUCUAGAGGUCUCUGAACAUGUGUGAUAGUAAGUAGGUAGCGAUGUUUCUGCAGCUGCUCACCACCCACCCAGGGAACCCUGGACCUGGUGGAGGUAAGAGGAAGACAGAAAGCAAAGCAACGCCUGCAGCAUACCCCAACCCUAACCCUAGCCCUGCCCAGCCCUGCAGCCCACAUGGGCUUCAUUCUCACACCAGUGCAGAAAGGCAAGUUUUAUUACCUCUACUUUAUGGGAAACUGAGGCUCAGAAAAGUGGAGUCUUGUUCGGGGUCACCCAGAUGGAACCUGGAUUGAGACCUAGGUCUCACCUGCCUGAUUUUCACCGUAGAAAGUCAGAACUACCUAGAGAAUGAAAUCAGUAAAAUACCUAGGAACAAGGUGUUUGUUCCCCAGCAUUUCAGCUGGGAGCUAUUUCCCUGCACAGAUAGGCUAGUGAGUUUUAUCUAUGCUGAAUUAUCCUGUGGUUCCACCAAGGUGACAUGUAGUCUAAGCUGCUUUAGGUGUACAUUAUUAAAAACGAGAGCCUAACAGUCAACAACAGUGGACUGCUUCCUAGUAAAUCUGGGUGACUAACUUUGCCUGUGCCCAAUGUUAACCCUCGAGGUAACACUAAGUGUUGAUAAUCACACAGACAUUAUCAAAGUGUCCAGUCAUCCCAGUGGCUGGAAAUCGGAUCUAGAACUGAAUACCAACUGAGACCGCGGAAGUCUCAGCGGUCCUGAUGGAAUCUGAAAGUCUGUCCCUCCCACAGCUCUAGCUCAGUUCUUCCUCCCUCUCUUUCCUUUUCUAUUAGUUUACAAAAGGCUUCUUUAAUUACCCAAGAGAUGCUUCAGAGUCAGCUGACUUUCCUUGCAGCAUUUCACAUGUUUACCCAAUUUUUCUCUGGCUCUCUCAAUUUGAUUAAUUGCAAAAAAUGAAAUAAAAAAGAUUUCCUCCAAGCAUGCAGCUGCUUUUGUGUGCAGAUGGAUCUUUUCAGCACAUUACAGAAACCAGCUGCCAGGCUGAGCUCUUAGCCCCGUGACAGUGAGAGCUUCAUCCUUCUCGAGCUCUUCUCUAAAAGGCAGACUGGGGCAGAGUGUCAGAAGCUAAUAAGGCAGACUGCCAGUCACUCGUGAUUAUCAGCCAGAUGCUCUGUCGUUCCCACCAUAGUUCCUUGAGACACGUCUCACUUACCGGUGCUCAGGGGCCAUUUCCACUAACGGCUCUGAUGGGGGCUCCCACACAUCAAGUUGUCGUUUUGUUCCUCUUGUCUUUCUUUUCCUGCUAGUAUAUAAAUUUUGCAUUUAAGGCUAGAAUUAACCAACCCUCAGUGAUUCAUAUAAAUAUUCUUUAUAUUAAUCUGAGAGGCCAGUCAAAUGCAAGUAAGUAGGCUUGUCUAACUAGUCAAAUCCAACAAGAUGUAUUCAAAAGUCUGAUCUGGACUUGAGUUAUUUUCACCAAUUCUGUGUCCAGUAUUCUUGAGUUUUCUAAAUCAUGAUUAAGAUCAAUCAUCCCAAGCGUAACCUAGAGUUGUGCUAUGAAGCAUGACAACAUUUGAUCAGAACAAACUGAUUCGGAAGAAACAUGGCCCCUCUCCAAGGAGCAGUUCAGCACCUUGUGGACAGAUUUCAGCUGCGUUCAAGAGCCCCUUGCCCAAAAAUAGCUCUCUUUGUCUACCAGCAAGUCCCAAAAUAUUUACAUGGCCCACACUAUUCUGAUUUGGGACAAGUCCUUGGAGCUUUGUUUCCUGGAAGGAGUGAGUGUUGCAUUUGUGUUUGCCUAGUCCCAGCAUAAGGAGGUGGGAGGAGGAGGGUGAGAAACGGAUAGAGCCAGGGAACAGGAAGGGGACUGGGCAGGCGAGGGCUCACAGGAGGCAGAGAUGAGAUGAUGCCUGGGCCAGGAACAGGCACUUGGAGAACACAGCCGGUGAUAGGAGGUUCAUUUAUGUCUGGAUGGGCAAAAUGCCCCCAAAGGUCCAAGUUGUCAACCUUAACUAAAGGAAGUUACCUGUUUUUGCCUGUGUUUAGCUUUGAAUAGACCAGCUCUUAUUUCUUAAACAGAAAGAUGGAUUGACAGAUAUUUGACAUGUUUUUAUUCUAUAAUGUGUGUCCAUCCUGCAAGCUCUUAAUAUUUAGUUAAAACAACACCACAUGGAAUUAGAGAGGCAGAAUUAGGGAAUGACAGCCCCUGUGUACCCAGGGUUCAAACGACACCUCACAAGGAACACACCCCUUCUUUCUUAGACCCUAAAAGGACACAGUGAAUUUGGCCUUUCCCUUGGUUAACCCAUUCUUAUCCAGUAAGGCACCACAUGUGCAACAAACCCUCAUUUCCCAAUGAGAAGAAUGCCCCUUCAAGGUUUUUUUGGUUGUCCAAUUUAAAUAAAUUGGGAAGGUAGAAUCACACUGGACACCGAAAUCAUCCGCAAAGGUAGCCUUGCGUUUUUAAAAUCAUACAUAUCAAACUAUUAUUGCUUUUUUCACUCUCAUGCCAUGAAGCAUGGGGAAGGCACCUGAUUCUUGCAGGUGGGUUGUGUUUAUAUCAUCACUAGAACCGCGUCUUUGAUUUCGCAGAGCCUCAUCUGUGGGCACUUUGACCUAAGUUGCUUGAAGUACACGUGUUUUAAAUCUCCCUGCACGAGCCCCUCACCGGAAGUCUUAUCGUGGGCCCCAGUUUCAUCACACACCCUGAAGGUGGGUGGGGUUUCCAGUCUGUGGUCGGCUGCUAGUCGUCUCCCACACACGUGAGGGAGGUGGACUCCGGGAGUGGCGACUGUGCUGUAGGCGUUUGCUUCUCUUCUCAGCAAUCCUUCCAGUGGCUGUGGGGUGAUGGGGGUGCCCGCCUGCAGAAAAGUGUCCUCAGCCAGUCUUCCUGAGCCACCAAAAAGGGACCCCGGUAACAUGGGAGAUGGAAAAGCUCAGCUGUCAGGCAAUUCUCUUUUCUAAAGAGAGACUUUUGAGGAACACAAUUUGCAUUGUGUUCGGGUGUAUCUACUAUUUUGGAGAGUCCUCUCUCCCCGUGUUCAGAAGACAGUUCAUCUUGUUCCCUCUCAAGGAAAGCUGUUCCUGGGUUCUACAGGAGAAUGGGUACUCACACCUUUUUGCAAAAGAAUACAUCCAUCAUGGAAAACAUGUUGUCAUUGUCCUUAAAGACUCUGGUCACCUGCAGCGUGGUCUGGGCUGAUGGUUCCAGUGGCCCUCAGCUGAAGAGCCCCAAGGCCAGGGCAGGUUCCGCAGGAAGGCUGGAAGGAGCAAUUUGCUUGGAAUGGCCUCUGAAGAGCCAAUCCAUUCAGGAUGGGAAACCACGCAGGCAAACGAGAAUUAAAUGCCGAGAAGGCCAGUACGAAUAGUGAAACUAACAGAGGAGAAUCUGAAAAAAAGAGAAACCUGGGUGAACUUUCACGGACAACCUCAGAGGACAACGAAGUGUUCGGAGAGGCAGAUGCGAACCAGAACAAUGGGACCUCCUCUCAGGACACAGCGGUGACUGACUCCAAGCGCACAGCGGACCCGAAGAAUGCCUGGCAGGAUGCCCACCCAGCUGACCCAGGGAGCCGCCCCCACUUGAUCCGCCUCUUUUCCCGAGAUGCCCCGGGGAGGGAGGACAACACCUUCAAAGACAGGCCCUCUGAGUCCGACGAGCUCCAGACCAUCCAAGAAGACAGUGCAGCCACCUCCGAGAGCCUGGAUGUGAUGGCGUCACAGAAGAGACCCUCCCAGAGGCACGGAUCCAAGUACCUGGCCACAGCAAGUACCAUGGACCAUGCCAGGCAUGGCUUCCUCCCAAGGCACAGAGACACGGGCAUCCUUGACUCCAUCGGGCGCUUCUUUGGCGGUGACAGGGGUGCGCCCAAGCGGGGCUCUGGCAAGGACUCACACCACCCGGCAAGAACUGCUCACUACGGCUCCCUGCCCCAGAAGUCACACGGCCGGACCCAAGAUGAAAACCCCGUAGUCCACUUCUUCAAGAACAUUGUGACGCCUCGCACACCACCCCCGUCGCAGGGAAAGGGGAGAGGACUGUCCCUGAGCAGAUUUAGCUGGGUAGGUGACGAACGCACUUCCAUCGGCUUCCUCUUCCGUCCCAGUCCUCACAGCCCCGCAACUUUUGUGUUCUGCUCUGUUUCGGUUGCUUCCUGGCCUCCUUUUCUCUCCUCUCGAGACCUCUCUGCCCACAGCUGGGAUCGGGCCGCCUUGUCUUCCACUGGGGAAAUGAAACGUGGUCUUCCCUUCCGGAAGGUCUGGUCUCUUGCUUCUGUGCCGGGGACCCAGCCCUGCAAGGCCAGAUCCUCUUCUCCCAGAGGGUUCCCAGGCGACGUGACUGGUCUCCCUCCCAGGGAGGGAGCAACACCACGUCCGAGAAAAUGUUUAACUUCCUCCAACACAACCAGUGCGAGAAGCCCCAGGAACCCGCAUGUGGAAGUGGGACUGGCUGGCCCGUCUCAGUGACCCCAGAUGCUGACACUGGGAAAAUGAUUCUGCUGAUGAACAGAAAAAGAGGCUAAAUAGAGUUGCUCGAUUUAUAAUAACCUCAUUAAUCCAAAGAUUUUUGUUUUGUAUGUGUUUAAAUAAUAAUUAAAACAUAGAUAUCAAGCCAUCCAGAAAAUCUUCCUUAGGAAUUUUAGGCUGGUUAAUACUGAAAGCAAACUUUCAAGGAAGGUUUAAAAUGGCCAAUUUGAACUUUCUAGUGAAAAAAUUUGGUGUCUGAGCCAAAUUAAAAUGCCAAUCAUUAUAUUCUAACCAAACUUACAGACUUUAGUUACUAGCAAAUACCAGAUAUGAUUCUUACUGUAUAAAAGUUAUAAUUUUAGAAUAAAAUGGAGGAAUAACCACCAA